CUGUCUCAAAAAAAAAAAAAAAAAGAGAGCGAGAGAGAAGAAAAAUUACAUAUAUAUUUCUAAACUUGCUCAUUUCCCUCAUCAACUGGAUUCAAGGGACUUCCUGGUAAGAGUUUGAGGAGAAUUAGGAGGCAGUUCCCCAGAGACAGCCUUGCAGACAGGAGGUUCUUUUCUCUGUAGGAGUUCACAAUGGCCUCAAUGGUAAGAGCUCUGCAACUGUGUUCCCAAGUUUGCUUGACUGAAGAGAUGUGCUGGAAGAGUCGCCCUAACUUCUUGUUUCUGGUUUUACAGUAUAAAAAUCAGUGCCUUUUCAUUUCCAAAUACCUCAUUGGCUUUUGUGCCUGGAGUGGGAAUCAAAGCGCUAACCAACCAUGGCACUGCCAACAUCAGCACAGACUGGGGGUUCGAGUCUCCACUUUUGUGCAAGGAAGUCAGAGGUGAACAUGACAAAGUCACUGCAGUCCAGGAGCUUAGAGUCUCUGGGUAAUCAGAGAAACAAGAUCCAUCUCUGUGCCUGACUCAGGCUUGGAUAACCUUGCACUUCUUUAAACAGCCAAGACACAGGAGGGGCUGAUCUGUUUCUCUCCGGAGUCUACUUUACCGGUAUCAUUAUCCUAACCCGAAAUGACUUUGGUCAUCCUACCCUGAAGCUCCAAGAUUGCUACGCCCAACUGAGCCAUGCCCACGUCUCAUUUUCCGGAGAACUCAGUGUUCUGUAUAACUCCUUUGCUGAGCCCAUGGAGAAACCCAUUUUAAAGAACUUAAAUGAAAUGCUCUGUCCCAUUAUUGCAAGUGAAGUCAAAGCGCUAAAUGCCAACCUCAGCACACUGGAGGUUUUAACCAAGAUUGACAACUACACUCUGCUGGAUUACUCCCUAAUCAGUUCUCCAGAAAUUACUGAGAACUACCUUGACCUGAACUUGAAGGGUGUAUUCUACCCACUGGAAAACCUCACCGACCCCCCCUUCUCACCAGUUCCUUUUGUGCUCCCAGAACGCAGCAACUCCAUGCUCUACAUUGGAAUCGCCGAGUAUUUCUUUAAAUCUGCGUCCUUUGCUCAUUUCACAGCUGGGGUUUUCAAUGUCACUCUCUCCACCGAAGAGAUUUCCAACCAUUUUGUUCAAAACUCUCAAGGCCUUGGCAACGUGCUCUCCCGGAUUGCAGAGAUCUACAUCUUGUCCCAGCCCUUCAUGGUGAGGAUCAUGGCCACAGAGCCUCCCAUAAUCAAUCUACAACCAGGCAAUUUCACCCUGGACAUCCCUGCCUCCAUCAUGAUGCUCACCCAACCCAAGAACUCCACAGUUGAAACCAUCGUUUCCAUGGACUUCGUUGCUAGUACCAGUGUUGGCCUGGUUAUUUUGGGACAAAGACUGGUCUGCUCCUUGUCUCUGAACAGAUUCCGCCUUGCUUUGCCAGAGUCCAAUCGCAGCAACAUUGAGGUCUUGAGGUUUGAAAAUAUUCUAUCGUCCAUUCUUCACUUUGGAGUCCUCCCACUGGCCAAUGCAAAAUUGCAGCAAGGAUUUCCUCUGUCCAAUCCACACAAAUUCUUAUUCGUCAAUUCAGAUAUUGAAGUUCUUGAGGGUUUCCUUUUGAUUUCCACCGACCUGAAGUAUGAAACAUCCUCAAAGCAGCAGCCAAGUUUCCACGUAUGGGAAGGUCUGAACCUGAUAAGCAGACAGUGGAGGGGGAAGUCAGCCCCUUGAUUGCCGGUUUGCAAUUCACCCCAGGAAGUAAAUGGUCCUUAAUCCUACAACUACUGUAAACCCAGAAGGGAAAGACAGUACACACUGGAAUUGUAAAGCCCUUGUGAAUUGCUUAGGCAGAAAGUUUUCUUUCUUAAGCCUUCAGGAACCCAGAAUAAGGCAGACUCUGUUAAAGGGAUAAAUAGAGGUGUCUGAAUGUGAGUGUAUGCAUGCUGCGUGUGUCUGUGUUUAUGUUUGUUUGUUUGUUUGGGGCAAGAAAGAUUCUAGGACAAGAGCUAGGCAUGUACUUCUGACCAGGUGGGUAAGCAACUCUAAGUCUGUAUUUGUAUUGGUCAUUCUCAGUGGAAAUCCCUUAGGCCCUCUAGUGGUUUUCCCCUACCUGCAUAUUGGUUUUCAUGUUUUAUAUUCACUGUUACUAUCUUCUGUGUUUAAUUAAAAUUGUUUUCUAUCAACUUCAA